AUGUCUCCGAGGUCACCCAGGUUUACGCGGGGCUUGGGCGGCGGAGACAGCGCCUUGGGCCCCCGGAUAGGGAAUGAGGAAGACACAGUCAUUAAACGGGAUGAAAGUGUACCUGUCUCAACAACUGGCUUCCUGCUCACAGGUCGAGAGCGAUCUUGGCUGUUGAAAAUAUGUGGAUCGGCAGCGCACACCUGCCGAUUCUGGCUGAUCUCGGAAUACGCUCAUGCAUCGGGGCCCCACACAGGAUCUCCAGACUCAGUGGGCACCUUUGGCCAGACAGUGGCUGUGCAGGUGGGUGUCGAGGGUGAGGGUGCGCGGCACCACGCUGAUGAAGCGCUGGAUCUCCAGCAGCACUGCGUUGGUGUAGGGCCAUUGCACGUGGUCGUCCGGGCUUGGGACAGGCCUCUGCCCUACCACAGGGUCCAGCUCCUGCCCCUUGGCUGGGGCAGAGGGAGGCUGUGCACUUCCGGGACCCUCCAGCCAUCUCCAAACCGCAGCCUCCCAUUCUGGGUCUCUCUGGCUCGCAGACCUGCCACCUCUGGGUACUUAAGCAGAAUGAGGAGCCCAUAUGGAGCACAGGGUGGUGCUCGUGGUUUCUGUGCCACCAAAAAAAAAAAAAAAAAAAAGUUGCAUCGUCAUUACCAACGUCUCCUCCUGGAAAUGGCUCUCUGGGUCUUGCUGUUUCUGUGGGCAGAGAAGAUGGGCUGCCGCGCGCCAGGCACCUGUUGGUGGGCGGCAUGGAUAGAGUUUAGGGAGCUGGGACCCAUGCCUUACCCAUCUGGCCAAGCAAUCGAUGAAAUCGCGGGGCUCCGCCGGCUGCCUCAUGUGCCAGUGUUGUUGGAUUUGCUCAGAGAUGAAGACCUGCAGCUCUGAAAAGUUUUGGAAGAUUUGGUGGUGCGGGCCCGGGAGCCAGUCCAUGAGAGACAGGCAAAUGUACAUCUGGAGAGACAGGGUCUCAACAAGGGCCCUGGACAUGCCCACUAGGCCUUAGUUUCCCUACAGGGACUUUGAUAUUGGAGGUUCUAGAACUCUUCCAAGAAUCUAACUGUCCCAUUGUAGGUACGUCUGUGUACUCGGGAUUUGGCAUAAGGCUGGACGCACAAGGGAGAGAUUGUGGCCGGCCCUCUCACCUCGCCCCAUUUGGAACUCAUGAUGCGGAAGUUGUCACUUAGGAGGUUCAGGACCUCAGGAACUCCGGGUCCCCGUAGCCAUAGCGGUUCCCGAAGACAAGAACAGGUAACACUGGAUACAGCAUUACCCAGUAGCCGCACGGGGUCAAACGGGGCUCCUGGGGGUAGGAACAGGACGGUGGUCAUAACGCGUGGUCCUGCCCCCAGCCAGCCCCAUGGGCUUACUGGCUUUCUUCCACCCAAAUACCUUCCAGUGGCCCCGUCUUGGCAGUGCAAGGGACUCUCCCACACCAGGCCCUUCCGCUCUCCCGGCCAGGCCGAAGCAAUGGUGGCUUGAAAUUCGUCUAGCAGACAAGCCGCCUCAUCCAGGACACGCGCCUCGAUGGUCCGCGUAUCCAACCCGAACUUCUUCGGCGCUCCAAGUGCAAAAUUGCGCAGUGUCCACCAGCACGGCCGGUUAGAAAACAAGAUUCCUGUGGUGGGGACGGGAAAGGAGGCGGGCCCGGGAACCGGCCACGCCCCAUCCAGGAAGCGCCGGGUCACUGGCUACAUCCCUUUCGGGGCCUCCGACUCCUGCGGCCGGCUUCGUUCGUUUUGCUGCCUUACCAGACCUCCAAGUGCCCUAUCCACACAUUGGCCCCGCCUUUGCUGGGCUCCAUCCCUGACCUAGGCUGGCUCUGGGACUUUGAAUCUUAGGCUCUUUUCUCCUGUUGGCUGCAGGAUGAACCUCCAUUCUAACCUUACGCUUUAGCGCCGCCCCGCCCUCUCUCGGCCGUUUGCACCUCAUUAGCUGGAGUCUCUAUUAGGCCCCGCCCCCAUUUGCCCGCCUCUACCAUUUACCCGCC